AAGCGUAGCCUCUUCUCCUUUACCAAGAUGGCGGCUUGUCCCUGUUUCGCCACAGUUCCUACCUUAUGAGCUCGGUUUUCUUAUGCUUAUAAGAGUGGAACAGAUGGAGGCAUCUUUGAAAAGUAAAGCGCCUCGUGUGAUACAGAGCUUCCCCUCCUGCAGAUAAGUCUCACAAACACUUAGCAUGUGUCUGUCCAGAGUUUCCUGUUAAAACACACUUUCAGAGGCGUGUAGUGUAUGAAUAAGUGCCAUUUUCAUGGCACAUAUUUUUCAUACAAUAUAUUCUUACAGUAACGAUACUGACAUUAUUAGGAUAUAUCCCAUUUGGAAUAUAUUGUCAAAUUAUUGUGUUUUAAAGUUAAAUAAUUCUCUGAUGCUUAGGCCGCCGCUCUGACAUUGUUAGAUACAUUUGUUUCCAUUUUCUAAGUAGACUUUUUAUUGAGGUAUAAUAAACAUGCACUUUUUAAUGUAUAUAGCUCAGUGAAUUUUCACUAACUGAACUCACUCAUAUAACCAGCAUUGAGAUAAAGAAGUGGAACGUUUUAUUUUUAGAGUUUAGAGUCUGAUUUUUUUUUUUUUCCUUUGAGACAGAGUUUUGUUCUUGUUGCCCAGGCUGGAGUGCAAUGGCGCGAUCUCGGCUCACCACAACCUCCGCCUCUUGGGUUCAAGCAUUUCUCCUGCCUCAGCCUCCCGAGUAGCUGGGAUUACAGGCAUGUGCCGCCACGCCCGGCUAAUUUUGUAUUUUUAGUAGAGACGGGGUUCCUCCAUGUUGGUCAGGCUGGUCUCGAACUCCCGACCUCAGGUAAUCCACCCACCUUGGCCUUUCAAGGUGCUGGGAUUACAGGCGUAAACCACUGUACCCGGCCUCUUCUGAUGUUUAUGGUUCUAAAACAGAGCUGUUACUCUUGUUCUGCUCAGAUGAGCUUGAUUUCCAUCCCUGUCCCCUGUCCCUUCUUUCCUUACCCCAACAUUUUCUUCUUGUUUCUUUCUGAAAAUAUAAACAGACAUACACAUUUCUAUUUCUGACUCUUUCUUACAGAAAGGUAGCAUACCCUGCACCUGCUGGCCUCCGUUGCUCUUUUCAUUAACUGUGUACCCCGAAGACUAUGCAUAGUAGUGUAUGGAGGCUUUCCUUCUACCUUUUAUGCUAUGUGUUGCUUCACUGCAUGGACACAAAGUGGUUUCUUCAGCCCAUCUGCAUAUUGAAGUUGUGUUACUUUCCAGAUUUUUUUUUUUUAGCUUUUUAUGUCUCGCUAUCUCUGCUGUUGCCCUUCUGAAGUCCAUUCAUCCCACACGUGCAGUAGCUGGAGUUUCCUUUUUAUCUAAUACUUGAGUUUCCCACUGCCAUACUCACCCCACGUUGAUGCCUAAUGUCUUCUUGAGGUUUCCUUUAGAGGGCACUCCUUACCUUUGGUGCCAGCCAUUCUGCUAUUCUGAUCCUACUUCCCCUCAUUACUGAUCUUCCUUCUCUGCCAUCCUGACCCCUUCCUGUCCUUGGAUGCCUUUGGAGUUGCAGAGAAGCUGUCUUUAUCUUCCUGGUGUGAUACUUGUUUUCUAAUAGUAGGAAAUAGUGUUUUCUUGUUCUGCCCAGUUUUCUCUCUUUAUAGAUGAGACAUCUAAGUUCCUGCUCCCUGGAUGUAUGUCAGUUUUUCUCUUACAUGGUAAUGUUCUGAUCUGAGUCCGGUAUCUCCAUUGUCUAACUUUGCAUAGAGGAACAUACCUGUGCUUUGGUGGGGACGUUGUGCUUGUAUUCGUGCAGUUUAAUGUUGAAUUAGCUCUUUGUGGAGACAGUUAUAUAAGUAAGCGUUUCUAGGGAGUCUUUAUAUCCAAAAGUGAGGCUUAAUCUCUGAAGAGUAGACUGAUAGGAAGAGAGUACCUGGAGAGAUGAUGCAGUCCCACCUUCUCAUGAGACAAAGGAGGAAGCAGGCCAAGUGAAGAGGGUGAUGUGCCAAGCAGUGUCAGCAGCAGAUCGCACAUUGGAGUGCCACAUGCUCUCCACCCUUGAGAGGAGAAAACCUGAAGACUUGGGUUUUCCUGAUGUGUGUUUUCUUGUUUGUAGAAAAGUAUUGUUUCUAUUUGGAUAGGACUGAGCCCAAGAUUAAUCUUUCAGAUUCUUAAGUAUUUUCCACCCAUGGCGUUAGCUAGCUUUGUAUCCAUAACAGAGUUCUUUAUAAACAUGAGCUAAGCUAAUUCUAGCUCAUAGAACUUUCCUAUGUAAAUUGUAGGAAGGAAAAAAUCAUCAAGUGUAAAUUGUUGCCCUGGGUCAAACUUCAAAUUAUUUUGUUUCUUGUAGUUUAAUGAGAUUUAUAGUGAGGAGAUGGAAGGGAUUUUUAAAUUGCAGGACUAAAGGGGAAUGGCCCUUCCUACAGCCAUUCUGUUCCCAUCCCCUUCCCAGGAACACCAUUACAGUUGGGGUGGGGGCCUGCGUGGGCUUCAAGCCCUGGUGAGGAGUAUGUGUGUGUGCAGGAGCUGCCAUGAAACACCUUUCAGCGGCUCAGGGUGGCAGACUAGUGUUACCAUGGCAGUUAGAGACAUCAGUAAACCCAUGGGUCAUACGGAUGCAUUUCCACCUAGAAGCAGUGGUUUGUUUCUUCAGUGAGUCAAAGAAACUUAAGAUGGAGGAGACCCUAAGGAGUCAUGUAAGUUAAAUGAUCACCCAGUGGAGAGUACACUUCACAGUGGGAAUAAGCUCUGCCCAUUUUUUUUCCUAGGUGCUAAUUCAGGAAAGCAUGCUCACUCUUAGUGAUCCUUUUCUUCAUGUUGAGAUGAAAUGUGUCUUCAGAAUUGUUCUUAGUUGUGCAGGCAACUGGACAGAACUCAGUCCCCCUUUAAAUGCUCUCCACAUGGUAAAGACAGCUCUUAUGUAUCUUGUUCUCAGUUUCCAAGGCUUGAAUAGGUUCAUGUAAAGUCAUCACCACUUCCUCAAAAGGAAAUUAACAAAAAAAAAUUUUAAUUCAGACGUCUUGCAGAUAACGUGGCAAUUGUAAUGAGAAUAGCACAGCAGAGAAAAUAAAUUUUGUGACUCUGUUUUUCACUGAUUUGUAGUACCUGGUGAUACUUAAGUGUCCUCUUUUCCCUCUCCAGGUGGAGGUAUUUUUGUUGAAAAGUAAAGAGCCUCAUAUAAUACAGAGCUUUCCCCUUCUGCUGAUAACUCUCACAAACACUUAGCAUAUGUCCAUCCAUAGUUUCCUAUUAAAACACACUUUGGGGGUAUGUGGUGUAGGAAUAUGUGCCAUUUUUCAUGGUCUUCCCUCCCGUCUUCACAUUCUACAGCUUCACAGCAGAAUUGUCUUUUCAAGUCCAUCUUUUACCCAGCUGUUCAUGUUGAUGCUUGUUGAGGACUGGGCUCUGGACUUCCUGUCCUUUUGCUAUUCUCAAUGACUUGAGUUUCCUUCUAGAGAGGUCUUAUGCAUGUACAAACAUGUAUAUCUUUUAACACGACUGGUUACAUAUCAACGUAACACAUAGCUGCAGGCCAGGCGCAGUGGCUCACACCUGUAAUCCCAGCACUUUGGGAGGCCAAGGCAGGCAGAUCACUGAGGCCAGGAGUUCAACACCAACCUGGCCAAUGUGGUAAAAUCCUGUCUCUACAAAAAAAUAUACAAAAAUUAGCCAGGCAUAGUGGCGCACACCUGUAGUCCAGCUACUUGGGAGGCUGAGGUGGGAGAAUCGCUUGAACCUGGGAGGCAGAGGUUGCAGUGAGCUGCGAUUGUGCUGCUGCACUCCAGCCUGGGCAACAGAGUAAGACCCUGUCUCAGAAAAAAAAAAAAAAAAGAAAGAAAGAAAUAGGCCGGGCGCGGUGGCUUAUGCCUGUAAUUCCAGCACUUUGGGAGACAGGCGGGUGGAUCACGGUGUCAGAAGUUUGAGACCAGCCUGGCCAACAAUGUGAAACCCUGUGUCUACUAAGAAUACAAAAAUCAGCCAGGUGUGGUGGCGCACGCCUGUAGUCCCAGCUACUCGGGAGGCUGAGGCAAGAGAAUCGCUUGAACCCAGGAGGCGGAGGUUUCGGUGAGCCAAGAUCACGCCACUGCACUCCAGCCUGGGCAGUAGAGUGAGACUCUGUCUCAAAACAACAACAACAAACUGCCUCUUCUUGUUCACUGACACUGGGUGUAUGGUUAAAGCCCCCUUAACUGACCUGUUUUGAGGCACAGAGGUUUAUUUAAUCACCAGUCAUUUGAUACAGGGUGAAGACCUAUUUGAAAUGGGACUGGCUGGAUUCUACAUGUUUUCUUUUUUUUUUUUUUUGGAAACAGGGUCUUGCUGUGUUGUCCAGGCUGGAGUGCAGUGGUGCCAUCAUGGCUCACUGCUCAACCCCUGGGGCUCAGGUGAUCCUCCCACCUCAGCUUCCACACUGAGUAACUGGCACUACAGGUGCAUACUACCAUGCCUGGCUAAUUUUUAUUUUUAUUUUUAUUUUUUAUUUUUUGGUAGAGACAGGGUUUCACCAUUGUAAACCCAGGAAAUCUGACAAGUCUCAGUUAAUUUAGAAAGCUUACUUUGCCAAGGGUGAGGACGCGCACCCGUGACCCAGCCUCAGGAGGUCCUGAUGACGUGUGCCCAAGGUGGGCAGAGCACAGUCUGGCUUUAUACAUUGUAGGGAGACAUGAGACAUCAGUCAGCAUAUACAGGACGAACAUUGGUUCGGUCUGGAGAGGCAGGAUGGCUCGAAGCAAAGGCAGGAAGACUCCAAGUGGGGAGGGGACUUCCAAGUCACAGGCAGGUAAGAGACAAAUGGUUGCAUUCUUUGGAGUUUCUGAUGAGCCUCUCCAAAGGAGGCAGUCAGAUACGCAUUUAUCUCAGUGAACAGAGGGGAGACUUUGAAGAGAAUGGGAAGCACGUUGGCCCUAAGCAGUUCCCAGCUAGACUUUUCCUUUUAACUUAGUGAUUUGGGGGCCCCAAGAUUUAUUUUCCUUUCAGACUAUGUUGCCUGUGUUGGUUUUGAACUCCUGGGCUCAAGCGAUCUACCCACCUCAACCUCCCAAAGUGCUGGGAUUACAGGCAUGAGCCACCAUGCCUGGCCACAUACUCUCUUCUUAUGUAAAUGAAAUUGAUAAUAUGUCGUCUAGGAUUUUCAGCAUUCAUUUAAGUGGAACAAAAAUUUAAGAAACUCAUAAUCAGUGUAGAUUCUCUGAGAUUUUAAAGGUUUUCCUCCAUUUGACUUUUUCUUUUAAACAAACAGGUCUUGCUCUUUUUCCCAGGCUGGAGUGCUGUGGCACGAUUGUAACUCACUGCAGCUUCAAAUUGGGUUCAAAUGAUCCUUCUGCCUCAGUCUCCUGAGUAACUAGGAUUACAGGCACAGGCUAAUUGUUUUUAUUUUUUAUUUUUUUAAGAAAUGAGGUCUCACUUUGUUGCCCAGGCUGGUCUCAAACUUUUGGCCUCAAGUGAUCCUUCUGCCUUGGCCUCCCAAAGUGCUAGGAUUAUAGGCAUGAGUCACCAUGUCCAGCCAUAAUUUUUUUAAGGCAACUUGUUUUUCUUGAAAUUUCAGUGUGGUAAAUUUAAUAUCCAUAGAUAAAUUUCUCUUCACUCCUUCAUUAUUUUGAAUUAUUUCUAAAUGUAGUUACAUUAACUAGUGAAACUGGCAUAAACAGGUUUGAGAGCAAGUAAAACUGAGUCUUACUAAGCACACAUCAUCACUGGUGGGGAUCGGUGUUCAGGGCACACUAGAAGGCACUCUGCUCAUGACAUCAAUUAAUAUUUUACUGUGGGGGUGGAGACUUGGUCAUUCAUCAGGUCGUUUAUGGAGGUCAGUGAUAGUGCUUUGUGUUCUGCCACCCUUUGUUUACCCAGUCCCGGACUGAACCAAUGCAAAUGUUUAAUCUUCUGACUCUACAAAAAUGCUACAGUGCACAUCAGGCACACUGCAGAGACACUGCAGGUUUGUGAUACCACCACAAGAAAGCCUGACAUCCCAAUAAAGCACAUCACAUGAGUUUUACGUUUCCCAGUGCAUAUAAAAGCUGUAACAUGUUUAGAAAAACAAUGGUAUAUACUUUAAUUUAAAAUAAUGGUUAAGGCUGGGCGCAGUGGCUCAGGCCUGUAAUCCAGCACAUUGGGAGGCCAAGGUGGGUGGAUCACCUGAGGUCAGGAGUUCGAGACCAGCCUGGCCAACAUGGUGAAACCCCGCCUCUACUAAAAGUACGAAAAUUAGCUGGGUGUGGCGGAGCACACCUGUAAUCCCAGCUACUUGGGAGGCUGAGGCGGGAGAGUCACUUGAACCCGGGAGGUGGAGGUUGCAGUAAGCCAAGAUCAAGACUGUGCCACUGCACUCCAGUCUGGGCAACUGAGUGAGACUCCAUCUCAAAAAAUAAUAAUAAAAUAUUGGUUAAAAAAUGCUCAUGAUCAUUGAGCCUUCAGCAAGUCUUAAUCUUUUUGCUGCUGGAAGGUCUCGCUUUGAUGUUGAUGGCUGCUGACUGAUCAGAGCAGAGGUUGCUACAUGUUGGGGUGACUGGCAAUUUUGUAAAAUCAGACAACAAUGAAGUUUACUGCAUUGAUUGACUCUUCCACAAAAGAUUUCUCUGUAGCACGUGAUGUUGUUUGAUUGCAUUUUCCCACAAUAGAACUACUUUCAGAAUUGGACUCAAUCCUCUCAAACACUGCCAUUGCUUUAUCAGCUAAGUUUAUGUAAUAUUCUAAAUCCUCUGUUGUCAUUUCAACAAUGUUCACAACAUCUUCAUUCAGCAUCUACUUCCUGAGUAGAUUCUAUCUUAGGAAACCACUUUCUCUGCUCAUCCAUAAGAAGCAACUCCUCAUCUGUUCACGUUUUAUCAUGAGAUUGCAGCAAUUCAGUCCCAUCUUCAGGCUCCACUUUUAAUUCUAGUUCUCUUGCUGUUUCUACCACACUUGCAGUUGCUUUCUCCACUGAAGUCUUGAACCCCUCAAAGUCAUGGCAUCCGGAAUGGUGAAUCCUUUACAGGAGGUUUUCAAUGGACUUUGCCCAAAUCCAUGAGAGGAAUAACUAUCUAUGGCAGCUGUAGCCUUAAAAAUAAUUUCUUAAGUAUUAAGUCUUGAAAGUCGAAAUUACUUCUUGAUCCAUGGGCUGCAGAAUGGCUGUUAGCAGGCAUGAAAACAACAUUCAUCUCCUUGUACAUCUCCAUCAGAGCUCUUGGGUGACCAGAUGCUUUGCCAAUCAGCAGUAAUGUUUUGAAAGGAAUCUUUUUUUUUUUUCUGGGCAGUAGAUCUUAACGGUGAGCUUAAAAUACUCAGUAAAUCGUUUUAAACAGAUGUGCUGUCAUCCAGGCUUUGUUUCAUUCAUACAGCACAGGCAGAGUAUAUUUAGUGUAAUUCUUCAGACCCCUAGGAUUUUCAGAAUGGUAAAUGAGCAUUGGCUUUAACAUAAAGUCACUGGCUGCACUAGCCCCUAACAAGAGAGUCAGCCUUUUGAAGCUUUGAAGGCUUCUCUUAGAAGCGAUCUAGCUAUUGGCUGGGCGCAGUAGCUCACGCCUGUAAUCCCAGCACUUCGGGAGGCUGAGGUGGGCGGAUCACGAGGUCAGGAGAUCGAGACCAUCCUGGCUAACACGGUGAAACCCCAUCUCUACUAAAAAUACAAAAAAUUAGCCGGGCGUGGUGGUGGGCGCCUGUAGUCCCAGCUACUCGGGAGGCUGAGGCAGGAGAAUGGUGUGAACCUGGGAGGCAGAGGUUACACUGAGCAGAGAUCAUGCCACUGCACUCCAGCCUGGGCCAUAGAGCGAGACUCUGUCUCAAGAAAAAAAAAAAAAAAGAAGCCAUCUAGCUAUCAAAGUCCUUAGAUGGCAUCUUCUUGCACUAUGAGGCUGUCUCAUUUACACUGAAAAUCUGUUUAGUGCAGCUACUUUCAUCAGUGACCUUAGCUAAAUCUUCAUAACUCACUGCAGCUUCUACAUCAGCACUUGCUGCUUCACCGUGCACUUUCAUGUUAGAGAGAUCUUAAACUUCAAGAACCAACCUCUGCUAGCUUGAGACAUUUUUUCCUGCAGCUUCCUCACCUCUCUCAGCCUUCAUGGAAUUAAAGAGAGUUAGGGCCUUGCUCUGGAUUAGGCUUUGGUUUAAGGGAAUUUUGAGACUGGUUUAAUCUUCUAGCCAGACCACUCAAACUUUCUCCUUAUCAGCGAUAAGGCUGUUUCGCUCUCUUACCAUUUAUGUGUUCACUGGAGUAGCACUUUUCCUUCAGCCUUUUUUCUUUGCAUUCACAGCUUGGCUAUUUGGUGCAAGAGGCCUAGCUUUUGGCGUGUCUUAGCUUUUAACAACUCUUCUUCACGUGCCUUCUUAAUCAUUUCUAGCUUUUGAUUUAAUAUGAGAGACGUGCAGCUCUUCCUUUCACUUGAACACUUAGAAGCAAUUGUUGGGUUAUUAAUUGGUUUCCCCUCAAUAUUGUGUCUAGGGAUCGGGCGGCAUGAGGAGAGGGAGAGAGAUGGGAGUGGCCAGUUGGAGCAGUCAGAACACACACAGCAUUGAUUGAUUAAGUUCUCUGCCUUGUAUGAGCGUGGUUUGUGGCACUCCAAAACAAUUACAGUAGUAACAUCAAGGAUUACAGAUCACCAUAACAGAUACAAUGACAAUGAAAACGUUUGAAAUAUUGCUAGAAUUACCAAAAUGUGCUGUUGGAAAAGAGGCAUGGAAAGACCUGCAGAGUUGCCAAAACCUUCAGCCUAUAAUAAACACAAUGUCUAAAAAACCCAAGUAAGAGAAGCACUGUAAGCUGAAGUGUGCCUCUAUCUUUGGGCACAUGUGUGAGAAAUUCUUAGAAGUAGGAAGUGUUAGAUCAAAGAAUAUUGAUGUUUUAAAUCUCAGUCCACAAUCAAAUAUGUACGCUCUCCAAAGAGACCACACCAAUUAUUCCUCCAGCCACACCUGUUUUCCCACACUUUUUUUUGAGUCUUCAGAUUUUAUUUUUGCCAAACUGAGGUGAAAUGUAGAAUCUUAUUCUACUUUUCACUUGCAUUUUAAAAUACAAAUUGAAUAAAUGUUUCCUGCAUUUCCAUGAAAGGCCUGCUUGUAUCUUUUGCCCAUUUUUUAAAAAUGGGUUAUUAAAGAGUCCUUUAGGAAAUACUGUAAACGUAACGUGCUCCUCUUUUCCCCAGAAAUGUUUGAGCCUGCCACGUGUGCCAUGUUUGUGUUUGUGGUAGAGGAGAUGCUUUCAUGAUUGAGAAGAAGACGCAUUUUAUACUCUUUUCCCCUAAUGUAAAUUUAUUCAUUAAACACAAAAGAUUUGUAAUAAAAUAUUUUUUCCUUAAGAUUGUUAUAUAAAGUUUACUAAUGAGAAAAACUCCCUUGUCAGUUUAUAGUUUAGCUUUGGUUUGAAAAUACAGACACUGUAGCACUGCUGUCCAAUAUGAGCCACAUAUAUUUAAAAUUUUCCAACAUCUGCCUUAAAAAUAUAAAAAUAAACAAGUGAAGUUAAUUUUAAUAAUAUUGUUUCACCCAAUGUAAGAUACUACCAUUUUACAUGUAAUCCAUCCUAAAACUAAUAAUAAAAUGUUUUAGAUAGUAUUUCUUGUACUAAAUCUUCAAAAUCUGAUGUAUAUUUUAGACUUACAGCACAUAUCAUUUUAAACUAGCCACGUGUGAAGGCUGUAGUGACAUGUGGCCAGUAGAUGUUGGCCAGCACAGCUCAAAAGAGUAGUCUAUUUCUAUGAAAAUCCAUCAAUUUAUUCUUUUGGACCUAACAUUUGUCCUAUCCUCUUUUUUAUUUUUUUGAGACAGGGUCUCACUUGGUCAGCCAGGCUGGAGUGCAGUGUCACGAUCUCAACUCAUUGCAACCCCCACCUCCUAGGCCCAAGCAAUUCUCCCACCUCAGCCUCCCGAGUAGCUGGGAUUACAGGCACGUGCCACCAUGCCUGGCUUAUUUAUUUAUUUAUUUUUAAGACGGAGUUUCACUCCUGUUGCACAGGCUGGAGUGCAAUGGCGCGAUCUCGGCUCACUGCAACCUCUGCCUCCCGGGUUCAAGCGAUUCUCCCACCUCAGCCUCCCGAGUAGCUGGGAUUACAGGCAUGCACCCCCAAGCCCGAGUAAUUUUGUGUUUUAGUAGAGAUGGGGUUUCUCCCUGUUGGUCAGGCUGAUCUCGAUCUCUCGACCUCAAGUGAUCCGCCCACCUCGGCCUCCCAAAGUGCUGGGAUUACAGGCGUGAGCCACCGCGCCCAGCCCCCCAUCUUAUUAAGAAAAUAAAUUGUAUUUAUCUGACACAUGUUCUUUAAUUAGGCUCUAAGUAAAUAUUAUUCUUUACUCAGCUGUAGAAAUAUGUGCUGAUUGUUUCUGUAUUUGUAAAAUUAAUGUAGUGGCAUACUCCACUAAAUGUAUUAAUUUAGUGGAAAGUAGUGAGUUUAGUGGUUUAGUGGAAUUAAAUGUUAGCAUUCCCAAACAGUGAGAUACCUAUUAAAGGGCAGGUUCUUUUAGAUACCAUUUUCCUUGAUCUUUUUAACAACUUGCAGAAAAGGCCCCAAAACUUAGAAAUGUGAAUUAUUAAAGUUGAGAGCUUAAACAACUAGCCAAGGUGACCCAAAUUAUAUCUGAGCAAGAUUCUGAAAGCAGGUAUCCUGGCAACAAGUUUGGUGUUCUUUAUACAAUUUGUUCUCAUUAUAGGUGCCUAUAAUGACUCGGAUAAAACACAAGUUACGUAUUUUCACCUUACCUAGAAAUACGUGAAUCAAAGAAAUAAGCCAGAGAACAGUGUCACUGGAGAAUAUACUAAGUUACCUUUUCUGUUACUUCCUGAAAAGUAGUGAAACUGACAGAAUUAGUUAGUGGAGAAAGAACAAGGCAAAUUUACAGGAAACCCUGGACUGCAAGGUCUUUGUUUCUGUCUCAUCUGAACUUUCGUGAGACUUUAUUUUAGGGCUGGGAGUUUAAUGUAAUAAUAUAUACUGUAAUAUAUAUUAGCAGUAAAUACAUGUGAGCCAAAGAAAAGUUGUUCCUUAUUAGAAUAUGCUACAAGUCAAAUUAAACUGAGUAUAAAUAAGCUUAAUUAUAAAAUUAGUUUGUGCUAAUAAAAAUGUAAUAUGAGCCACAUAUAAUUUUAAAUUUUCAGCUUUCAAAUGGGAUGGAAACAUUUCUUUGACCUGACUUUGACCACCACACUCAGUAUGGGAGUGCAAAUUGUGCUAAACUUAGCUCCCAUCCCAUGGUGCCAAUAACUUCCUAUAAGACUGCACUGCUGCCAAGGAAGUGGUGGGCGCCUGUCCUCCACAUCUCUGCUCCCACAGCCUUGGAGAUGACCCCUGGUCCGCUGCUCCUCCUAACCCCUUCAGCAUGGCUCCACUGCAGCGGGUUCCUGUCAGGUGAUAAGUUAAAGCAAAGAGAGGAGUAGGCUGCAUAAAUUGUAUACCUCUGUUUAUCCAUGUUAUCCACUGACAAUUAGGUUCUUAAAAAUUUGUUGACUAUUACUAGCAGUGCAGUGAGAUGAGCAUUCUUGUACAUAUUUCCUUUUGCCCAGGAAAGCUUUUUCCUGAAGUACGUCUCCAGAAGUGGGAUCGUUCGCUCGUGGAGUAUUUGCUUCUUAAGCCUUAAUAGGCCUUGCAAAUGGUGUCAAAUAAGGACCUAGUUUUUCCCUCCUACUGUAGAUAACCAGUUUUCCCAGAGCCAUUGAUUGCAUCAUCCAUCUCCCUGCUGAUCCACACGACCACAUCUGAGGCAGGCAAUGUCAGUGUCUGUGGUGUCUGCGUUGGGCCCACUCUGCUGCUCCCUUGUUCUCUGUGUCUGUCCCCGGCACUAGCACCACAGCCUGAAUUACUGACACUGGAGAGAGCAAGCCCUCCUCCACGUUGUUUUCUUCAGAGUUAUAUUAGCUGUUCUUGGUCCUUGAUCUUUUGUAUAAAUUUUGUUGUGUAAAUAUGAUUGUAUUUGUAACUAUUCUAAAAAUGGUGUAUAUAAAUAAUUUUUUUUACAAUUCAGUGUUUGCAAUGCAACAUUAUAAAAAUUACAUAUAGAAAACUUGUAUAAAUAAAAAUUGUAUAAAAUCUGGUUGUAAAAUUCCAUACACACACAUACCUUUUGGGAUUUAAGUUACAUUUGCAUUGAAUUUCUAGUCUAAUUAGGGGAGAAUUACUAUCCAUGAUUAAGUCUUUCUUUAGAUGACCAUGGCCUGUCUCCAUUUAUUAAGGUCAUUUCUGUAUUUUGACAAAGGUUUUUAUAAGUUCUAUAAAUCACAUUUUUUUUCUUAAUUAGAUUUUAAAAAAUUUUUUUAGAGGGGUGGAGAGGGGACAGAGUCUCACGCUGUUGCUCACGCGGCAGUGCAGUGGCGUGAUCUUGGUUCACUGCAGCAUCCGCCUCCUGGGUUCAAGCGAUUCUCGUGUCUCAGCCCCCCAAGUAGCUGGGACUACAGGCAUGCAUCACCACACCCGGCUUAGAUUUAUUUUUAAUAGUUUGUUGCUGGUGUUUUGGAAACAUAAUUGAUUGUGUGUAUUGGUUUUAUUUCCAGAAAACUUACUGAACUUUUUAAUUAGUUCUAAUAGUGUGUCCAUACAUCCUCCUGGAUUUUCUUCCAGCACAGUUAUAUUGUCUGUGAAUACUGGCAGUUUUGGUUCAUUUUCAAUUCUGGUAACUUUCUUUUCUUGCCAUACUGCCCUGGCUUAUAUUCCUAGUUGCUAUUAGGAAUGGGUUAAUUAGUUGAGAUUCUUCAUUUGAAUUUUUUUUUUUUUGGAGAUGGAGUCUUGCUCUGUUGCCCAGGCUGGAGUGCAGUGGCACCAUCUUGUUUCACUGCAACCUCCACCUCCCGGGUUCAAGCAAUCCUCCUGCCUCAGCCUCCCAAGUAGCUGGGAGUACAGGCAUGUGCCACCAUGCCCGGCUAAUGUUUGUAUGUUUAGUAGAGACGGAGUUUCGCCAUAUUGGCCAGGCUGGUCUCGAACUCUUGACCUCAGGUAUCUGCCUGCCUCAGCCUCCCAAAGUGCUGGGAUUACAGGCACGAGCCACCGUGCCCAGCCUAUUUGAAUCUUUUGAAAUGAUCAAAUUAUCUUUGCCCCUCAUGCUGUUAAUGUGGCGAGUAACUUUACUCUGUUUUUCUAAUAUUGUACCCCCCCACAUUACUGGAUUAAACUUCAUCGUGAUAAUAUUUGUUUUUCUAUUUCUGGGUCAGUUUGCAAGAUUGUUUCAGGCUUUGGCUUUUAAAUACCUAGGUGAGAUUCACCUACUCCUUUGUCUGUGAUGAGUCCAAGCCCCCUAGCUUUGUGUGGGAGAUAAUCUCUGAAAGCUUCCUUACAAAAGCAUUUGGAGACCCGCCUUUUUGUUGUAUUAUUUUGUUGUUGUUGUUUUUUGGUUUUUUUUGAGAUGGAGUUUCACUUUUGUUUCCCAGACUGGAGUGCAAUGGCGUGGUCUCGGCCCACGGCAACCUCCACCUCCCAGGUACAAGCGAUUCUCCUGCCUCGGCCUCCUGAGUAGCUGGGAUUACAGGCAUGCACCACCACGCCCAACUAAUUUUGCAUUUUUAGUAGAGAUAGGGUUUCAUCAUGUUGGUCAGGCUGGUCUCGAACUCCCAACCUCAGGUGAUCCGCCCGCCUCGGCCUCCCAAAGUGCUGGGAUUAUAGGCGUGAGCCACCUCGCCCGGCCUUGUUGUAAGUUUUAUAUUUGUUUCUUUGAAGAUUGGGGAAGGUUGGUUAUUGAAACUAUAUUUCUAACUCAGUUUGGGUAACUUAUUUUUCUAGAAUUUGCCCAUUUCAUCUGUUUUCGAGUUUUUGACACUACUCUUCUCAAUAGAAUUCUUACAUGAUUUUUCAAAGUCUCCAUUUUAGCUGUAGUUUUUGACCCCCUUUUAAUUCUUAAUAUUGCCUACUUAUACUGUCCUUUUUUCAGGAAUCAUUUUUGCCAGAGAUUGAACUUGUCUUUUAAAAAAUUUGGAUGUAGGUUUUGUUUAUCCUUUGUGGUAUAUGUCUUUUAGUUCAUUAAUAUCUUAUCUUUAUUUCCUUCUACCUUUCUUUUGUUUAUUCUGGUGUUUUUUGUUCUAGUUUCAGUAGUGGAUGAUUAGCUUAUUUUAUUUUUUUCCUCUUCACUAAUAGGAUGGCUUAAAGUUACAAGGCUUUAAGCAACAAUCUUGUUUCAUUCCACAAGGUGGGAUAUAUAAUUGCUUAAUGGCUUAGUUUUAAAUGUUUUCAGAUUUCUUCCUUGUUCCAUGAGUUACUUAGAAGCAAGUUUUAAAACUUAUAUAGUCUUUAAAUUUUUAAGUUGAGUUCUAAUUGAGUGGUGGUCUGAGAAUGUUACUAUGAUUUAAUUCUUUACUAUUUGUUUAAUUUUUUUUUUUUUUUUAGCUCCUGGCCAGGUUUUAUGGUUUUUUAAAAAGGUGUCACUUUUAAUCAUGUGUUCAAUAAAGUAGAUUUAUUAAUUGUGUUUGCAUCCUCUAUACAUUUUCCAAUCCCAUAACCUGUGUUACCAAGAGAGUUGGGUCAGUCUCACCCUUUAACCUUGGAUAUAUCAAUUUCUCCUAGUAACCUUCAGUUUUUACUUUAUAUGUUUUGCAGCUAUGUUAUUAGAUACAUGUAAUCAGAGUUACUGAAUUUUUAAGUUCUUGACCUUCUCUGUUCUUAAUAAUGAUUUUUAUCCUACAGUCUGUGUUAUCUGAAAAUAAUAUAACCAACUUUCAUAUGGUUAGUAUUUGCUCGGAGUACUUCUUCCAUCUCUUUAUUUCAGCCUAUAUGUCUGUAUGGUUUAGGACUGUUGAAUGGCCUAUAGCUGCUGUUAGAGUUGGUCAGUUUAGUCUGUUAACACGUAUUUAGAUUACUGAUGGGUUUGAAUUCAUUCCUCUCAUCAGUUUUGUGUUUUAUUUACCUUGCUUUUUCAUUGCUUCUUUUACUUUUCUUGCCUCCUAUUCUUUUUUCUUGUUUUCUCUCUUUUCUUUAACAAUUAUUAAUACAGUAUAAUGUAACCAGUAAUAAUGUACAUCGUAAUGAAUACCGCUGAACCUACCACCUAAUCCAAGAUCUAGAACAUUGCCAAUAACUUCCAUUUGAGUAAGAGUUUAGUUUGAAUGUUAAAAACUCUUUGUUUUUCCUAGAUUGUCUUUAAAUUUUUAACAUUCAUUCUCAACAAGGGCUAAAAUUAGUAUCUCUAGCCUCUCCCCAAAUAAUAAGAAUCUUGAAACCUUGCAACUUCAUAUCCCCCUUCCACCUUAUAUAUUAUUGCUGCCUAAGCAUUUUAAUUCUGUCUUUUAUUUUAUUUUGUACUUGCAUAUUCUGCUUACGUACCUAUCUAUAAUUUAAUUCCCUUCAAAUUUUAUUGUUGAUAUUAGUAUAGGGUCACCACUUGUUUCACUUUAUCUAGGUUGCUGGUUUAUCAGUAUUCCUUCUUUCUGGUCUCUCUGGCUUUCAUUUUCUUGCUGAAAUAUGUCCUUUAGUAGGUCUGUCAGCAGGGAUCUAUUGGUAGUAGUUGCUUUAUCUUUGAAUAUGUCUAUUCUCAUUCUUAAAUGAAAAAGAAUUCUUAAAUCCAAAUUGACAGUUAUUUCUUUCGCCAUAAUUUAUAUAUAGCCAUUAUCCUCUGGUAUGUAUUGUUUUAAGUGGUCUGCCUUUGGUCUCAUAGUAUUCUUUAUGAGUAACCUGUCUUUUCUCUCUAGUUGCUUUUAAGGUCCUGCUCUUGUCUUUGGUGCUCUGAGGUUACUCUGUAGUGUGUUUUGAUUUGGAUUAGUUUAAAUUAUCCUGCUAGACACCUUCUCUGUCUUUUUUGGGAUGAGGGAAGAAUGUUGUAUCAUUAAAUCUUAGAAUUUUCUCAGCUAUUUUAAAAAAUGUUUCUUCUCUGUUCUUUGGAUUUUUUCUUUUCUCUUUUUGUUUUGGAACUCCAGUUAUAGACAUAUGUUAGAGUUUCUCAUUCCAUGGUUCUUAGCUCUUUCAUUCGUUCCAUCUCUCGAUUUUUUUUCUAAAAUGUCACCUUUAUGUCUCUUAUGCUUUUUUAUUGUCUCAAUCUUAGUUCUGUCUCCCGAAGUUCUUGAGUCUAAUCCUACUUCUAAUCCAUCCUUCCUUCUUUUUGAGCUUUGGGCUUUUAGCCUCUCUACCAUUUGUGCUGAUCUGUGGGUAUCCUUUUUAGCCUGGUAUGAGGUUUAUUCUUUCCUGAGGCGGGGUGGGGGGGAAUUGCUUUCUGUUUUGUUAAUAUCUCAGUUUGGGCUAGGGGUUCCUGGACAAAUGGGCUUGGUUGUAGAGUACUAGUCCAUUGUCCCUACAGCUCAAGAGAUGCUUCUGUCUGCCAGCUCAGGAUAGUCAGAGAAGGCAUCCUGUAGUCCCCUCUACACUAGUGGGCUUUUCUUCUUCUUUUUUUGAUCUACCUAUCUUCUGGUAAGUGUAGCCCUUUUGGGGAUCAUGACUUUAUGGAAUAGGAGGGUAUCUCUUCUCACCUCCUACCUUGAGCAGACCCAAACUUCUCCCCCGUCCCUUUGAGGGCUGAAAACUCAAAUGUCACAGACAGACGUUCACACUUCAUUUGGUCUGAAUAUUGCUAGCCAUGGAAUUUCUAAAAUUUGCUUCUACGAACUAUUUAUUAGUUUCAGUGUGCUAAGCCUGCUGGGAGGAAAUGCUGGUUGUGAGCAUCAGCACAGAAGCAUUCUGGACGGUUAUUAGCACAAAGUUAGCAUAUGAUUUUGUAAUCUCUUCUGCUAACAGUGUUUUUUAAACUAACUCUUUACGGUGUCCUGUGUACUAGGUACUGUGCCUGUGCUGACUUCCUAGCUUUAUUGGAAGUUCCUUGACAGCGGACCGAAUCCCUACCCGUUACUCUUUCUCCAUCUCCCUCUGCAGUGCUGAGCCCUCAAAAACAAAACAGCAACAAAAAACACACUUGCACUAGUUGCUGAUUGGUUAAUCCCCACGGAAAGGUUACCAACAAACCACAGCAGUGACACAGAAGGGAAUGCCUAUUUCCACAUCUAGGGAGGCCCACCUGCCCAGUUCCGUGCUGCUGACUUAGAGCACGGCUUUGCUGAUGAUAUCCUUGGCUCCUUCUCUGCGUCAAGCCGCAGGUGUUCUCUGCCUUCUGUGAUUCUGCUCCCCUCCCUAGGUGGUGUCAUGAAGUGCAUGGUAUUUCUGCUGGCUCCUAGGCUUUUCCCCUGACCUUGCACAUACAGUUGCCUGCUCCACUUCCCCACCUGCCCAGUCAGGGCAUCACACCCCCUUAUCCAUCCAGUCUUCCUUGAAUUUUACCCACCUCAGUGAGGGCAGCUCUUCCCAGUCACUCAGGCCAAGAACCUGUGUCUUUCUUAACUUCUUUUACACCCCUCUUCUGGUCAAUAAGGAACUUCUUGGUGCUUCUUUCUGAAUAUAUACCAAAUCUGGCCAUUUAUUUCCUCCAUUAUGCCCACCAUAAUGCAAGCCAUUGUCAUCUUUAGACUGAACUAUAGUAGGCCUCCCCUGCCCUCCCCUCCCCUGCCACUUAGUGUCAGUGUUCCACGAAAAAAAAAAAAACACGUCUGAUCCUGCCUUCUGCUGCUUGCAGCCCCCACCCAGCUCCCACCAUCCUCAACAGCACCCGUGGCCUGGCUGCAGGCUGUGCGGACCUGACCCCAUUCCCUGGGUAAGGCUGGGUGUGCCCCUACCUCUUCCCCUGUGUGGGACGGUCUUGUCCCCAGAUACCUGUAGUUGAUCCUGUGCCCUAUGCAGGAUUCUGUUGACCUGCGACUUUGCCAGAGGUUCAGACUGACAUCUCUACAGAUUGCUCGACUCCCUUUAUACCCUUAAAAGAAACAGUGGCAGUUAUCACUUAGUAAACACAAUGGAUGCAGAAGUGACAAGUCCUUCCCGGAGGGUGGAGACCCCGAGAGUAGGGAUUCCGUUCCGCCCAGUCCUGCGUAUCCACCGUGGGCUCAGAGGCCACACACCGGUUCUUUUGCGUGUAUACAUCUAUGUAGAGAUGGAGCCAUAAGUAAUACACGCUUUAAAGGAAGGGGAUUUUACAUUUUGGGGGGGAGAUUAAGUUGAUUGCCAAGGAAUCGGGUGGGGAUAGUUUAUAAAAGUGAGGGACAUAAGGAAUAGGCACGCAGGAAUGAGGGAAUGAAAGCCCUGGAGCCGCCUGGGAGCCUCACUGCGCUGUAGGACCUCGUGCCAGUGUGGCCAUCCGUUUACGAUGUGGUGGGCAUCCUUUGAGGUUUUUCUUCUGAUUUUGGGGAGGUGGGCGGUACUGGUGACAUCUGCUUCCAGAGCAGCCGUCCUUCCUGCUCCCUUUCUGGUCUUCGGUUGUUUCCACUCGGGUUCUUGCGGGGCGCGCUCCCUCUGCUUUCUGGAGGUGAUUAAUUUCCCAACUCCUCGGCACCGCCUUCCCCACCCGAAAAAAGGAUGCAGAACCACGCCUGCAGUUGGGUGGGCCUCCCGGGUGCUGGGCGGCCCGGGGCGGCGGGGACCCCAGCGGCGGGGCGGGCGGGCGCUGACGUGUCCAGGCGGGAUUGGGCCGCCGCCCUAUAUAGCAGCCGGGGCCCGGGCGCCGCGCCUCGGAGCGUCCCGGCUUCUCCCGCGCGGGGGGCGAGUAAGCCAGCGGCAGGACCAGCGGGCGGGGGCCCACGAACACAUGCCUCACUCCUGUCAGCAGUUCCACCUUUUCAUGGUUGAGGAGCACAUGUGGUCGCCAGCCUCCCAUCUCCAGAGUCCCCUAAGGCAAGGUGACUCACCCUCCUACUUCACAGAGUUCUUGGUCCUCCCCAGACAGCCUUUGAAGGUUCCUUUCAAUCCUGCGAUUUCAUGACCUGGUUUCUAGAUCCCCAGUGGAUUAGAAAGGACUGAAGGACUUUUACAGGCUAACAGCAAGAAGAACAAAGUAACUGCAAAAUAGACGGAGAAUUCUUGAAGACGGUAGCUCUUGGUCACCAUAAGCGCUGCAGAGACCCCGAGGUCCACAUUCUGUUGUAGGUCAGAGCCCAGCACAACAACCCUUCUUCUGGUUCAGCCGCCCAGCGGUUAUGUGGGGUACGGGAAAGAUGAUCCAGCCAUGCAGGAGAGCACCAGUGGUUCUGUGAGGAUUUUACUUCAAAAUACAAAAGCUGGCAGGCUGACAGAGGCGGCCUCAGGACGGACCUUCUGGCUACUGACCGUUUUGCUGUGGUUUUCCCGGAUUGUGUGUAGGUGUGAGAUCAACCAUGAGUUCCGUUGCAGUUUUGACCCAAGAGAGUUUUGCUGAACACCGAAGUGGGCUGGUUCCGCAACAAAUCAAAGUUGCCACUCUAAAUUCAGAAGAGGAGAGCGACCCUCCAACCUACAAGGAUGCCUUCCCUCCACUUCCUGAGAAAGCUGCUUGCCUGGAAAGUGCCCAGGAACCCGCUGGAGCCUGGGGGAACAAGAUCCGACCCAUCAAGGCUUCUGUCAUCACUCAGGUGUUCCAUGUACCCCUGGAGGAGAGAAAAUACAAGGAUAUGAACCAGUUUGGAGAAGGUGAACAAGCAAAAAUCUGCCUUGAGAUCAUGCAGAGAACUGGUGCUCACUUGGAGCUGUCUUUGGCCAAAGACCAAGGCCUCUCCAUCAUGGUGUCAGGAAAGCUGGAUGCUGUCAUGAAAGCUCGGAAGGACAUUGUUGCUAGACUGCAGACUCAGGCCUCAGCAACUGUUGCCAUUCCCAAAGAACACCAUCGCUUUGUUAUUGGCAAAAAUGGAGAGAAACUGCAAGACUUGGAGCUAAAAACUGCAACCAAAAUCCAGAUCCCACGCCCAGAUGACCCCAGCAAUCAGAUCAAGAUCACUGGCACCAAAGAGGGCAUCGAGAAAGCUCGCCAUGAAGUCUUACUCAUCUCUGCCGAGCAGGACAAACGUGCUGUGGAGAGGCUAGAAGUAGAAAAGGCAUUCCACCCCUUCAUCGCUGGGCCGUAUAAUAGACUGGUUGGCGAGAUCAUGCAGGAGACAGGCACGCGCAUCAACAUCCCCCCACCCAGCGUGAACCGGACAGAGAUUGUCUUCACUGGAGAGAAGGAACAGUUGGCUCAGGCUGUGGCUCGCAUCAAGAAGAUUUAUGAGGAGAAGAAAAAGAAGACUACAACCAUUGCAGUGGAAGUGAAGAAAUCCCAACACAAGUAUGUCAUUGGGCCCAAGGGCAAUUCAUUGCAGGAGAUCCUUGAGAGAACUGGAGUUUCCGUUGAGAUCCCACCCUCAGACAGCAUCUCUGAGACUGUAAUACUUCGAGGCGAACCUGAAAAGUUAGGUCAGGCGUUGACUGAAGUCUAUGCCAAGGCCAAUAGCUUCACCGUCUCCUCUGUCGCCGCCCCUUCCUGGCUUCACCGUUUCAUCAUUGGCAAGAAAGGGCAGAACCUGGCCAAAAUCACUCAGCAGAUGCCAAAGGUUCACAUCGAGUUCACAGAGGGCGAAGACAAGAUCACCCUGGAGGGCCCUACAGAGGAUGUCAAUGUGGCCCAGGAACAGAUAGAAGGCAUGGUCAAAGAUUUGAUUAACCGGAUGGACUAUGUGGAGAUCAACAUCGACCACAAGUUCCACAGGCACCUCAUUGGGAAGAGCGGUGCCAACAUAAACAGAAUCAAAGACCAGUACAAGGUGUCCGUGCGCAUCCCUCCUGACAGUGAGAAGAGCAAUUUGAUCCGCAUCGAGGGGGACCCACAGGGCGUGCAGCAGGCCAAGCGAGAGCUGCUGGAGCUUGCAUCUCGCAUGGAAAAUGAGCGUACCAAGGAUCUAAUCAUUGAGCAAAGAUUUCAUCGCACAAUCAUUGGGCAGAAGGGUGAACGGAUCCGUGAAAUUCGUGACAAAUUCCCAGAGGUCAUCAUUAACUUUCCAGACCCAGCACAAAAAAGUGACAUUGUCCAGCUCAGAGGACCUAAGAAUGAGGUGGAAAAAUGCACAAAAUACAUGCAGAAGAUGGUGGCAGAUCUGGUGGAAAAUAGCUAUUCAAUUUCUGUUCCGAUCUUCAAACAGUUUCACAAGAAUAUCAUUGGGAAAGGAGGCGCAAACAUUAAAAAGAUUCGUGAAGAAAGCAACACCAAAAUCGACCUUCCAGCAGAGAAUAGCAAUUCAGAGACCAUUAUCAUCACAGGCAAGCGAGCCAACUGCGAAGCUGCCCGGAGCAGGAUUCUGUCUAUUCAGAAAGACCUGGCCAACAUAGCCGAGGUAGAGGUCUCCAUCCCUGCCAAGCUGCACAACUCCCUCAUUGGCACCAAGGGCCGUCUGAUCCGCUCCAUCAUGGAGGAGUGCGGCGGGGUCCACAUUCACUUUCCCGUGGAAGGUUCAGGAAGCGACACCGUUGUUAUCAGGGGCCCUUCCUCGGAUGUGGAGAAGGCCAAGAAGCAGCUCCUGCAUCUGGCGGAGGAGAAGCAAACCAAGAGUUUCACUGUUGACAUCCGCGCCAAGCCAGAAUACCACAAAUUCCUCAUCGGCAAGGGGGGCGGCAAAAUUCGCAAGGUGCGCGACAGCACUGGAGCACGUGUCAUCUUCCCUGCGGCUGAGGACAAGGACCAGGACCUGAUCACCAUCAUUGGAAAGGAGGACGCCGUCCGAGAGGCACAGAAGGAGCUGGAGGCCUUGAUCCAAAACCUGGAUAAUGUGGUGGAAGACUCCAUGCUGGUGGACCCCAAGCACCACCGCCACUUCGUCAUCCGCAGAGGCCAGGUCUUGCGGGAGAUUGCUGAAGAGUAUGGCGGGGUGAUGGUCAGCUUCCCACGCUCUGGCACACAGAGCGACAAAGUCACCCUCAAGGGCGCCAAGGACUGUGUGGAGGCAGCCAAGAAACGCAUUCAGGAGAUCAUUGAGGACCUGGAAGCUCAGGUGACAUUAGAAUGUGCUAUACCCCAGAAAUUCCAUCGAUCUGUCAUGGGCCCCAAAGGUUCCAGAAUCCAGCAGAUUACUCGGGAUUUCAGUGUUCAAAUUAAAUUCCCAGACAGAGAGGAGAACGCAGUUCACAGUACAGAGCCAGUUGUCCAGGAGAAUGGGGACGAAGCUGGGGAGGGGAGAGAGGCUAAAGAUUGUGACCCCGGCUCUCCAAGGAGGUGUGACAUCAUCAUCAUCUCUGGCCGGAAAGAAAAGUGUGAGGCUGCCAAGGAAGCUCUGGAGGCAUUGGUUCCUGUCACCAUUGAAGUAGAGGUGCCCUUUGACCUUCACCGUUACGUUAUUGGGCAGAAAGGAAGUGGGAUCCGCAAGAUGAUGGAUGAGUUUGAGGUGAACAUACAUGUCCCGGCACCUGAGCUGCAGUCUGACAUCAUCGCCAUCACGGGCCUCGCUGCAAAUUUGGACCGGGCCAAGGCUGGACUGCUGGAGCGUGUGAAGGAGCUACAGGCCGAGCAGGAGGACCGGGCUUUAAGGAGUUUUAAGCUGAGUGUCACUGUAGACCCCAAAUACCAUCCCAAGAUUAUCGGGAGAAAGGGGGCAGUAAUUACCCAAAUCCGGUUGGAGCAUGACGUGAACAUCCAGUUUCCUGAUAAGGACGAUGGGAACCAGCCCCAGGACCAAAUUACCAUCACAGGGUACGAAAAGAACACAGAAGCUGCCAGGGAUGCUAUACUGAGAAUUGUGGGUGAACUUGAGCAGAUGGUUUCUGAGGACGUCCCGCUGGACCACCGCGUUCACGCCCGCAUCAUUGGUGCCCGCGGCAAAGCCAUUCGCAAAAUCAUGGACGAAUUCAAGGUGGACAUUCGCUUCCCACAGAGCGGAGCCCCAGACCCCAACUGCGUCACUGUGACGGGGCUCCCAGAGAAUGUGGAGGAAGCCAUCGACCACAUCCUCAAUCUGGAGGAGGAAUACCUAGCUGACGUGGUGGACAGUGAGGCGCUGCAGGUAUACAUGAAACCCCCAGCACACGAAGAGGCCAAGGCACCUUCCAGAGGCUUUGUGGUGCGGGACGCACCCUGGACCGCCAGCAGCAGUGAGAAGGCUCCUGACAUGAGCAGCUCUGAGGAAUUUCCCAGCUUUGGGGCUCAGGUGGCUCCCAAGACCCUCCCUUGGGGCCCCAAACGAUAAUGAUCAAAAAGAACAGAACCCUCUCCAGCCUGCUGACCCAAACCCAACCACACAAUGGUUUGUCUCAAUCUGACCCAGCGGCUGGACCCUCCGUAAAUUGUUGACGCUCUUCCCCCUUCCCGAGGUCCCGCAGGGAGCCUAGCGCCUGGCUGUGUGUGCGGCCGCUCCUCCAGGCCUGGCCGUGCCCGCUCAGGACCUGCUCCACUGUUUAACACUAAACCAAGGUCAUGAGCAUUCGUGCUAAGAUAACAGACUCCAGCUCCUGGUCCACCCGGCAUGUCAGUCAGCACUCUGGCCUUCAUCACGAGAGCUCCGCAGCCGUGGCUAGGAUUCCACUUCCUGUGUCAUGACCUCAGGAAAUAAACGUCCUUGACUUUAUAAAAGCCAAACGUUUGCCCUCUUCCUUUCCCACCUCCCUCCUGCCAGUUUCCCUUGGUCCAGACAGUCCUGUUUGUGGAGUGCAAUCAGCCUCCUCCAGCUGCCAGAGCGCCUCAGCACAGGUGUCAGGGUGCAAGGAAGACCUGGCAAUGGACAGCAGGAGGCAGGUUCCUGGAGCUGGGGGGUGACCUGAGAGGCAGAGGGUGACGGGUUCUCAGGCAGUCCUGAUUUUACCUGCCGUGGGGUCUGAAAGCACCAAGGGUCCCUGCCCCUACCUCCACUGCCAGACCCUCAGCCUGAGGUCUGGUGAGUGGAGCCUGGAGGCAAGGUGGUAGGCACCAUCUGGGUCCCCUGUGGCCGUCACAGUGUCUGCUGUGAUUGAGAUGCGCACAGGUUGGGGGAGGUAGGGCCUUACGCUUGUCCUCAGUGGGGGCAGUUUGCCUUAGAUGACAGCUGGGCUCUUCUUCACACCACCUGCAGCCCCUCCCUGCCCCUGCCCUAGCUGCUGUGUGUUCAGUUGCCUUCUUUCUACCUCAGCCGGCGUGGAGUGGUCUCUGUGCAGUUAGUGCCACCCCACACACCCGUCUCUUGAUUGAGAUGUUUCUGGUGGUUAUGGGUUUCCCGUGGAGCUGGGGGUGGGCGCCGUGUACCUAAGCUGGAGGCUGGCGCUCUCCCUCAGCACAGGUGGGUCAGUGGCCAGCAGGCCCAUCUGGAGUGGGAGUGGGCACUUCCACCCCGCCCACAGGCCAUCCGGCUGUGCAGGCCAGCCCCUAGGAGCAGGUCCCGGGUGACUGGCAGUUUUCACGGUCUAGGGCCGAGACGAUGGCAUGGGGCCUAGAGCAUGAGGUAGAGCAGAAUGCAGACCACGCCGCUGGAUGCCGAGAGACCCUGCUCUCCGAGGGAGGCAUCUGUGUCAUGCUGUGAGGGCUGAGGACGGGGCCCUAGUCUCUGGUUUUCUGGUCUUAACAUCCUUAUCUGUGUCCGCCACGGAGGUGACUGAGCUGCUAGCGAGUUGUCCUGUCCCAGGUACUUGAGUUUUGGAAAAGCUGACUCACGCCCAUCCAUCUCACAGCCCUUCCCUGGGGACAGUCGCUUCCGCCUUGACACCUCACUCUCAGUUGAAUAACUCAAGCUUGGUCAUCUUCAGACUCGAAUUCUUGAGUAGACCCAGACGGCUUAGCCCAAGUCUAGUUGCAGCUGCCUCGGCAAGUCCCCAUUUGCUCAGGCAGCCCUGAAUGGGCCUGUUUACAGGAAUGGUAAAUUGGGAUUGGAAGGAAUAUAGCUUCCAGCUUCAUAGGCUAGGGUGACCACGGCUUAGGAAACAGGGAAAGAAAGCAAGGCCCUUUUCCUGCCUUUCCCGGGAUCUGUCUACUCCACCUCCACGGGGGAGGCCAGUGGGGAAGGGCUGUCACCUCUUCCCCAUCUGCAUGAGUUCUGGAACUCUGUCCUGUUGGCUGCUUGCUUCCAGCUCCCCCCAAUCUCCAUCGCAGCGGGUUCCUCCUGUCUUUUCUACAGUGUCAUAAAACAUCCUGCCCCUACCCUCUCCCAAAGGUCAAUUUUAAUUCUCACCAAGUUUUGCACAUCUCUGUAUGUCGCUUGAUGUCUUAGACGCGAGCCCUUUCCUAAACUGUUCAGCGCUCUCUUUUCCUUUGGGUGGUUGUUGCAAGGGUGAUGACAUGACUGUCCCCAGGCCUGUCUCCCUGAAGCGUCUGUGCUGUCAGGACAGCCCUGGGCAGAGAUGAGGCAGGGGUGAGGCGUGCGUGUGCUUUUCCUCCUUGUUGGAUGUCUUCCAUAUCAUCUGUUUCCAUAGCUACAAUCCAUCCCUUGGCCUUAACUUUGGAAUUUGGAGAUUAUAUGCAAACAUGUGUAAAGGCUCAUGAAUAUGGAUGACACUGGAAUUUUAUAAAUUCUAAAAUAAAACCCGAAACCAGA